CUCUCUCUCUCUGUCUCUCUCUCCCUUUCCCUCCUACCACUGCCUCUUCCUCCCGCUCUCUACCUCCCUGCAGCGCCAAGCCGGCUCCCCAACCUGGUCUGCUGAACGCAAACCGCUGAGAGUUUGCUGCACCGCCCCCUGGGGCCCCUGGCUGCCGAGUCCCGCUAAGGCAAAGACGCCAGCAAGCGAGGAAGCGCAGCGGAAGAAAAACAAGCGGGCGCGCGAGGGGAGCCCCAGGAGGGCUGCCGAGUGGCUGGCAGGCGGCUCCCGCCCCUCCCGGGUGGCCUCGCCGGCGGCUGACGGCCCGGAGGACGCGCGCUCCGAAAAGUUAGACUCCGGGCGGCGGCGCGCUACGCCGCGUCCCCUCGCGUCCCUUCCUCGCUGCGCUCCGGGAAAGGAACUUGUUCCUUCGGCCCCAGGAUUGGGGAGUGUGCCGCGGGGCCGAGGGUGGGGAACAGCCAGAGGGAGACGCGAACCAGGCCGCUGGCGGAGGGCUCAGGGGGAGCGCAGAGGCGACGGCCCCCAUGCCGGCGGCCAACAUGAUGGAGAACCGGCCGCUGCCCGCCCUGCAGGUGCCCGAGCCGCAGGGUGCGCCCGAGGGCAGCCCGGUCUGGUCCAGUUCGUCGACCCCCACGCUUCGCCGCCGGCGCUUCAAGAUGCGCCGCAUGAAGAACGUACAGGAGCAGAGCCUGGAGGCCGGGCUGGCCCGGGACCUGCCCGCCGUCUUGGCCCCCGGCAAGGAGUUCCUGCAGCUGCCGUCCAUCGAGAUCACGCCCUCCAGCGACGAGGACACCCCGUGGUCCAACUGCUCCACACCCAGCGCGUCCCCGCGCCGAAAACGCUUCCUCCUCCGCAAGUGGCUGAGGGUGAGGGAGCGGAAGGAGUGCAGUGAAAGCAGCAGCCAACAGAGCAGUCAGCAGAGCAGCCACGAUGAUGAUUCUAGCAGGUUCCUGAGUCCUCGAGCGCGGGAAGAAAGCACUGCCAGUAACUCCAACCGCAGCACGCCGGCCUGCUCGCCCAUCCUCCGGAAGCGGUCUCGCUCGCCAACCCCGCAGAACCAGGACGGAGACACCAUGGUGGAGAAGGGCUCAGAUCACUCCUCGGACAAGUCCCCGUCCACACCGGAGCAGGGCGUGCAGCGCAGCUGCUCCUCCCAGUCCGGCCGGAGCGGCGGCAAGAAUUCCAAGAAAAGCCAGAGUUGGUAUAAUGUGUUAAGCCCCACCUACAAGCAGAGAAAUGAAGACUUCAGAAAGCUCUUUAAGCAGCUUCCAGACACGGAGCGCCUCAUUGUUGAUUACUCAUGUGCACUCCAAAGAGACAUUCUCCUUCAGGGCCGACUCUACCUCUCUGAAAAUUGGAUCUGCUUCUACAGCAACAUCUUCCGCUGGGAAACUCUGCUGACAGUCCGUUUGAAAGACAUCUGUUCCAUGACUAAAGAAAAAACAGCUCGCCUCAUUCCCAAUGCCAUCCAAGUUUGCACUGAUUCAGAAAAGCACUUCUUCACUUCGUUUGGGGCCCGGGAUAGGACAUAUAUGAUGAUGUUCCGGCUCUGGCAGAAUGCUCUCCUUGAAAAGCCUCUGUGUCCCAAGGAGCUCUGGCACUUUGUUCACCAGUGCUAUGGGAACGAAUUGGGCCUGACCAGUGAUGACGAGGACUACGUGCCCCCUGACGACGACUUCAACACAAUGGGAUACUGUGAAGAGAUCCCUGUGGAAGAGAAUGAAGUGAAUGACAGCUCAUCCAAGAGCAGCAUAGAGACCAAGCCAGAUGCCAGUCCACAGCUGCCCAAGAAAUCCAUCACCAACAGCACACUAACAUCCACAGGGAGCAGUGAGGCCCCCGUCUCGUUUGAUGGGCUGCCCCUGGAGGAAGAGGCGCUGGAGGGAGACGGGUCCCUGGAAAAGGAGCUCGCCAUUGACAACAUCAUGGGGGAGAAGAUUGAGAUGAUCGCUCCUGUGAACUCCCCUUCACUGGACUUCAAUGACAAUGAGGACAUCCCCACUGAGCUCAGUGACUCUUCCGACACACACGAUGAAGGAGAGGUCCAGGCCUUCUAUGAGGACCUGAGUGGCCGGCAGUACGUGAAUGAAGUCUUCAACUUCAGCGUGGACAAGCUCUAUGACCUCCUCUUCACCAACUCGCCCUUCCAGCGGGAUUUCAUGGAGCAGCGGCGCUUCUCUGAUAUCAUCUUCCAUCCAUGGAAAAAGGAGGAGAAUGGAAACCAGAGCCGAGUGAUUCUUUACACCAUCACCCUUACCAACCCUCUGGCUCCCAAAACUGCCACUGUCAGGGAGACACAGACCAUGUACAAGGCGAGCCAGGAGAGUGAAUGUUACGUGAUAGAUGCCGAAGUCCUCACCCACGACGUGCCCUACCAUGACUACUUCUACACAAUCAAUCGCUACACGCUCACCCGUGUGGCUCGGAACAAGAGCCGACUCAGGGUCUCCACAGAGCUGCGCUAUCGAAAACAGCCCUGGGGGUUAGUGAAAACGUUCAUCGAGAAGAACUUCUGGAGUGGGCUGGAGGACUACUUCCGCCAUUUAGAGAGCGAGCUGGCCAAAACGGAGAGCACUUAUUUGGCUGAGAUGCACAGACAAUCUCCCAAAGAGAAGGCCAGCAAGACUACAACGGUGCGGAGGAGGAAGCGUCCCCAUGCCCACCUGCGAGUCCCUCACCUGGAAGAGGUGAUGAGCCCGGUCACCACGCCCACAGAUGAGGAUGUGGGCCACAGGAUCAAACAUGUGGCAGGUUCCACACAGACGCGGCAUAUCCCGGAGGACACCCCCAACGGUUUCCACCUGCAGAGCGUGUCCAAGCUGCUGCUGGUUAUCAGCUGUGUUCUGGUGCUGCUGGUCAUCCUUAACAUGAUGCUCUUCUACAAACUCUGGAUGUUGGAAUACACCACGCAGACCCUCACUGCCUGGCAGGGUCUAAGGCUCCAAGAAAGGGGUCUGGGAGCCCAGGACAGUUCGCUGAGCAUAACUCCAGCUGCUGGGGUACCCCUUCUUCUACCCCACAGGUUACCCCAGUCUCAGACAGAAUGGGCCCAGCUCUUAGAGUCCCAACAAAAGUACCACGAUACUGAGCUCCAAAAAUGGAGGGAAAUCAUCAAAUCCUCAGUGAUGCUCCUUGACCAGAUGAAGGACUCGCUCAUCAACCUUCAGAACGGCAUCAGGUCCCGCGACUACACGUCGGAAAGUGAAGAAAAGAGGAAUCGCUAUCAUUGACAAGGCAGGAACAGGGUGGCUGCAAGAGGCCUGUGCAAUACAUGUACAUAGACCAUAUAAAUAUAUAUAUAUAAAUAUAUAUAUAUACAGAAUAUAAAUAUAUAUAUUAUAUACAGAUUUUAAAAAAGAGAUAAUGCCUAUGUACCAGGGAGAAGGAGCGGGCCCUCCCGCGCCCUGUGCUGGCCGGAGCAGCGUUUUCUUAUGGUGGAGCAGCUGAGGAGGGCAGGAACCGCCUCUCAGCACCGACCUCCCCUGAUCUCCCUCCUCCCACCCUCUGUUCCCCACCCCUUCCCUUGCUGGCCAUUCUUGGCUUUUAGAAGGGAAAUGUUGAGCCAAAGUUAUGCCUGCGAAGACCCUAAGGUCUCAAAAAGAAGUCUUAAGACGGCAUUGCUUAAGGUGCUUCAUUCCCUAAUCCCCUUUUGAUUUGUUUCCAAAAUAAAAGAGAAUCUUUUCUUCCCUACCCCAGGCUUCCCCAGGCAUUCUCUUGGGAACACAGAAGCAUCAAGGGAGCCCAGUCUAAACUCCUAGGGUUGGCCGCCCACUUGAUCCAGACCGUACUGAGUGUCAGAUGGAGAGGAUGCUUGGAAAGCUAGGAAGGCUGCAUUGUGUGGUGGCAGGCUCCCGAGACUCGUGUUCUGAAGGAUACUCUCCUCCAUCACCCCUGCACCUUCCUCCGACCUGUGUAGGGUGUGGACCCAGUAAGGGCUGGGAAUUUCUUACUUUCCCACCCGCUUUCUCUCUGGUCUUCUCCCAGGCUGGAUCUGGGCGAAGUGUCACUUUUUAGUGCCUAAAGUCCUAUUGUUUCUCUGUGCCCUAAGAGCACAUUGUUUAUUAGCCAGGGUGGAGCGUUUUCGACCUUAUUAAACCUCUUUUAGUGCUUCUAAGCAAGUCAGGUCUGUGGCUCUGAGGCCUUCACUUAGAGCUGUCAGUGUGAUUUCCAGGAUGAGUCAGGGUGUGCUGGGCCCUCCAGGAUUUGAGAGAGGGAGAGAAGGCCCUUGCCACGUCCGGGGUGCAGGGUCUACCCACAGAACACUGUGAGUGGUGAGCACCAAGAUGGGUUGCCAGCCUCAUUUGCUCUUUGAACGAACCAACAUUAGCCAGUGGAGACGACUGUCUGAGACAGUUUGCACAUAGAAAAAGCAUCUGAGCCACUGGAGGGAAGGAUUUGGCAAAGGUGCAUGUGUUUGGGCAGGAAAAGGCCAAGUGAAAUCUAUGCCCUACGGGAGCCAUUCCCAAUCCUGAGUUUCUCAGACUUGGCAAUGGGGGUUCUGGCGGGGGUUGGAGUACAAAUCCUGCUCUGGUCUCUGGCCCCACAGAGGUGUAAGAUCAUUAAGAAGUAGAAGGCACUAGCUUCAAAGAGUGAGACAUUCAGGGCCUUUUCAGCAUUGGCCCACUAGCACCAUGCAUUUAUCUGAAUUCACGGGGCCCUCUGGGCACAUUCAUCAUCCCUCAUACACUAACUACUGUUUCUUCAUGUAAUGACCAAAAGAGUCCCACCAGCUCCAGGCAGAGCUUGUGGAGAUUCAUGAAAGAGUCAUAGCCAGUUUGGCAUGCAGAGGUCUUCAGUCUUGCUUAUUCUUCUCCUGGGCUUCUUGACACAGGGGCAGAAGAAACCCCAGAUGUCCCAGAUGUCCCAGAACAUCAGCCCAAAAGACAGAAGAUUUUAUCACUCAUCUACCCCAAAGAUAAAGUUGUAUUUUUUUCUUAGAAUGGCCUUUAAUUCCCUGUGGCAAUUACAGUUUUUGACUUUUCCAUGUGAGAAUAAGGCCUUGGUAUUUCCCUAAGGGCAGGAUCAGAAAACAGGAAGGUCCAUGCCCAGGUGAUCCUCCAAGGGAGGAGGGUGAGGAGGCUCCAGGGCAUGAGCUAGAGUGGAUAUUCCUCCCCUAGAAGAGGAGAUGGGAGGAAAUGCAGUUUCAUGUAAUCCCUGUGAAGAGUGCCUAUGCCCACAGCCCAGUGGGUCCUUGUUCAGUUCUUGUCCAGGCCUUUGGGUGAGGGACACUGGUAGGGAUCAAGGCUCAUGGGCUCUGAGCCAAAGAAGGAGGCAUGGUGCAGACUGCUGGAAAUCUCCCCCUUGGCACAGCCAGAAGCCAAAACUAUUCCCAGAAAGUUUUGAAUGCAAAACUUGUAGAUUCCUGAAUUUAUUCCAUACAUAAUUAUUUCCUUAAGUUAUUUAAUUAUUAAAGGUGCCACGGUGGGACCUUUGGGAUGACUUAAAAAGGGUUCUUUGUUGGGAGUCAAGUGACAGAGCAGACCUGGCCGCAGGGAGUUGUUCUGCUUCUGCUUUACCUCUCAGGACCAUUCCCAGGAGGAAAAGGUGGCAGAGAGGGCAGUACUGAGUAUGUCAGAAGAGCCCUCCUGGUUUUUUAGCGAUUUGAACCCACUAGACAAUGUGUGCACAUAGGGAAUGUCCUUUAAGAAUCAUGGAUCUCUUGUAGGCUCUCUGUGUUCCAAUAAUUUUUUGACUAUCAUACCAGGAAAAAACCAACAACUCUAUUCAUUCCCAAACAAAAUCUCUUCCCCCUUAGUCAAUAGCUUGCGAAAGACAUCUUAACUCACCCUUGCAGAUAAGUCUUGGAGUGAAACAAAUAAAUAGCAUUGUAUUCCUGGCCAUUUGCCUGGCUAGUUGCUGUCUACAAGGGAGCAUCAAAACAUCACUACUUCUUAUGUAACUUCUUCCAGCCAGUGCUUUUAUUGUUCGUUUUAGUUUACUGGGGACACACAGGAGUCUUUCUGUAAUGACUUAUGUGGUAAAAUGUUUGAGAGUUUGCACUCAAUUUUAAAGAAUUUGCAGUUUCUAACAAGGUGAAGAACAGCUAUAGGAUCUAAAGUUCCAUUACAGCUUACUGUGAAAGAAUUGACAAGACUGGCCUCAGACAAGCUAAUCAUGGUGCGACUCUCUCCCUUCCUCAUCCACCUCUUUGGGGACAAGAGGAUUACAUCUCAGGCCAGCAAGAUCAGCUGCUUGAAGCUCUGUGUAAGAGCACUGCACUGACGGUUUGGAGACCUGAGCCUGGGUCCUGACUUUUCCAUUGACUAAGCUCUGUGGCCUUGGGCAAGUCACUCCCCCUCUCUGAGCUUCAGUAUCCUCCUGUCACAGGAGGGAGUUGGGCUAGAUCAUCUUUAAGGUAGGUUCUAGCUUUGACAUCAUCUUGGGGGUUAGGCCAGAGGCUGGGAAGACUGGGUGGACUUUCUCAAUUGCUCUGCCAGGAGGGAACAAGCCCAGAGGCUGAAGCUUCCCAGUAUUUAGAGGUGUGGUAGGGCAGUGUCUGCAUUCCCAGGAGACCCAGGGUGAUUAAAAUUUAUUCUUUAGGUGGCUAGGAGGGCUGGGGAGGCCCAGUGGAAGAGAGAGAGAGAGAGAGAGAGAGAGAGAGAGAGAGAGAGAGAGAUCGAGCUUGAUGUAUUGCUCAGUAUUCACUUAGAAGGGUUUCUUUCUCUUUGGCCUAGUUUGUGAAGGGAUCUUCCUUUGGACUUUCUCUAAGUUGGGAGAAGAACAUUCUUUUCAAUGGAGCUCAUCUUCUAUCUCUAGGGUCUGUUCAGCCUUUCAUCUAUCCAUCCUUCCUCUUUAUUGGUAGAAGAAACAGUGGAGAGUAGCCACUUCUGGUUCUAGCACUUCUCUUUUGUUAAGAUAGGGUUUGGAUUUAGUAUGAAGCUUUGGCUAAAACCCUUGGGUUUGCCUUAGAACACUGACACUAAGAACCUGGAAUGACAUGGGGAGGACAAAGAGAGCUCAAGAGGAAUGCUUUGUGAGAAGUGGAUUCUCUCCGUGUCCCUGCCCCCCACCCAAACUUGAACUAUACCUAUUACAUUUCCAGGCAGUAUCCCUAAGAUGAGAUCCUGGAGAAAGGACUAGGGGAAGUAUCUUUCUGGAUGCUUGUGGUCCCAGAAGGGUACUUUCUGUGUCAUACCAUGCCACUUCUUUAAGCUCUUCAGGGCAGCCAAAGCCAGCCCUUUUCUCCUACUGCCCCCAGGAGAAAUAGCACUCUUCUCCCUUCCCCCAGAUGGCAGGGCUCUGGCCUCCCUACACCUCAUACCCUGCCUGCCUCCUCCAGGAGGAAUCUCCGGGGCCCCUUCCUGACUCUCCCCACCUUCGCCACUUGUCUCUAGGCUAUGGGACAAUCAUCCCAUUCACCACUUGACAUCCUUGACAUCCUUGACUUUCAUUCCCCCAACCUCCAGCAGGUUGGCCCCAAUCCUCUUCACCUCUGUGUUUUCUUCUAGAAGAUGCAUUUUGGGUCUGAGAGGAGCAUUUUCCUGGAAGGCCAUCUUUUAAGGCCCCUGCUUGCUGUCAUAGUGCAGAGCAGAAACUUGCACACUAUUUAGAGAGCUCCCUUCCCACCUCUCUGCCCAGCCUUGUUACCUCACUUCUGCUCUGGCCAUGGCUGUGAAGGGCCCAGCCAGCUCCCUGUUUUGAUGUUCUGUGCAACAGCUCCGGGGUCUUGUGACUGGAGAUCCUCAACAGGCCCUGGAGCCAGGACUGGAGUCUUGGCAGCUGAUGAGCAGCACCUUGCCGGCCAGGAGGAGCUGAUGCUGACGAUCUCCCCAACAUCUGAAGGCUUAAAGAACAUUGUCGUUCUUCAGCCCUCCUUGCUUCUCUCAAUACAAUAAGACAUUGCAGAAGCAAAAGGGUGGCCUCUGCUCCAGGCAAGGCAGCUGGCUCUGUCUGGGGCAUCGGCCUGGGGCUUGGGUGCCACGUGCUGAGAUUGCAUAGUCAAAACAGCCAUUUUUGCCAACAAUAGCUUGUGGCUCCCCACAUUUUCCUACCCUGCACUCAAGGGCCAGACCACUCUCUGCAUGGACCAGACCAUCUUCCCAAACCCAUGGUGCUUUUUCCCCAACUCAACCUAGACUCCAAGGUGGGGAGGGAUGGGUCAGAGGCCAUAGUGGCCCCUGGAUAAUCCUGACGUGGGGUGGAGUGGGGUGAGGCAGAGGGAGCAGCCCCAACACCUGCACUGGGCCAUCUAUGGGAAAGAACACGGGUCGAGUGCAGUCGAGUUGUCUGGCCAUCUGUAUUUGGAUCUAUAACUGUACUUUGCCUGGCGCUGUGCGCAAGGUCAGAAAACUUACUGCUAGUACCUAGAAACACACAAGGCUGCCCAGCCAAAUCUUAAUGUAAAGUAGCUAGAGCCAUGGAAGUACAGUAUGAAUUAAAAAGAAAAAAGUAUUGAACUACAA